AUGACGAGGUUAGGAACAAUAUCGCUGACGGUCGCGGUGUCCCGUUUUAAUUUAGAGGGCGCCAGCAACACGUCAGUGAGGGAGAUUCAGAAGCCGCCGGGCAUUUCUAGGUUUUCUCCUCCUCGAGCAAAUCACGGUCUGCGCCUUCCGCGGCUCUGGGAACAGGUGAGCCGUGCGGCGGCGCCCGCGGGACGCGCUCAGGUGCCGGUCCCCGCCCGCCGGCCCCUCCCUGCAGCACGCGGUCCGGGCCCAGGUGCCGGGGCCCAGGUGCCGGCGCCCAGGUGCGCGGGGCACGGGGCUGCAGCUCCGCUCGGCAUCCGACAGCGGGCGCCGCUGCAGCAGCUCGCGGGCCGCGGAGCUGAACGGCUUCGCGAGUUGGGGCAGCUCCUCGCGCUCGGCCCUGCUCGGCGGCGAGAGCUCCGCCUGGGCGCCGCGUUCCUACAGCCGCCGGAGCCGCCAGGCGCCGAGGGAACGGACAGACCUCCGCGCACCCUUGCCGACCGGGGCGGGCAGAGGCGGGCAAGCGGCGAACGCCUGGGAGCGCGGAGAGCCAGGCCAGCCCGGAGCGCGCCGGGGACACCCUGUGCGCCCCGAGUCCCGGCACCAUGCGACCCGCCGCGCGUCCUCGCGGGCCCGGGGCUUCGCUCUUCGCUCGCUGAGCCCCUGCGCUCGCCACCACGGAAACUCGGAAAGAGGAGGCGAGGCUGUGGGGAGCGGCGCGGAGACGGACUAGACUUCCCCUCCGCCCCCAAGAGGCUGCCGGUCCCCGGUUCCCUGGGCUUCUCCAGCUUUAUCAUGAACCUGGCGCAAGGUUGGCUUUAG